GCAUUGAACUGAAUCUCUAGUCCCUGACACCAUGAGAUACUAUGGCAGCUACUACAGAGGCCUGGGAUAUGGCUGUGGAGGCUUUGGUGGUCUGGGCUAUGGCUGUGGCUGUGGAGGCUACAGAUAUGGCUCUGGCUAUGGAGGCUAUAGAUAUGGCUGCUGCCGCCCAUCAUGCCGUGAAGGAUAUGGAUUCUCUGGAUUCUACUAAAAAACUUGCUGAUUCUCAUACUCUAACUCCAAGAUCUUGCCCGUAUGCUUCAGCAAGGCGAACACUUUUCUCAAUGUAGAGAAAAUACCUACCAUUUUUUGGCUUCAUGCUCCAGAAGGAAC